GCGGACGCCGGCGACUUCUGGGCCCAUCCUCUGCUUCAAGCUCCUCUCAGGUUCCCUCUCUCGGGUGUUGACACUCCGUCUCCUCGUGGAAGUGGAGGAGCCGGGUGUGGACGGUCCCACGAGUCAAGUAAACAGGGCAGAGGAAGACGUCUGUGGUGGAAGAGGCUGUAGUAGUGUUGUCAGGGAAAAGAGAGAGCGGCUCUCUUUGUAUGGGACGGGGGUCAGGGAAAGAAGAUUUUCUGUUAAAGUGUGAGUAGGAGUUUGACAAACUGGAAGGAUGGUGGCAAAGAGGGCUUUCUAAAGAGCGGUGGCAGCAAGUGUGAAUGCUGGGGUUCCUGGAAAGAGACCGCAGUUGUGACAGCAUCUCGAGGCCUCCAGACGGUCAUCCAAAGGGAUUUCUUUCCUGAUGUGGAGAAGCUCCAGGCACAGAAGGAGUACCUGGAAGCCGAGGAGAAUGGAGACUUGGAACGGAUGCGCCAGAUUGCCAUCAAGUUUGGCUCUGCCUUGGGCAAGAUGUCCCGGGAGCCCCCGCCACCCUAUGUGACUCCAGCCACAUUUGAAACCCCUGAGGUGCAUGCAGGCACUGGAGUGGUGGGCAACAAGCCCAGGCCCCGCGGCCGAGGCCUGGAGGAUGCAGGAGAGGCUGGAGAGGAGGAGGAGAAGGAGCCGCUGCCCAGCCUAGAUGUCUUCCUGAGCCGCUACACGAGUGAGGACAAUGCCUCCUUCCAGGAGAUCAUGGAGGUGGCCAAGGAGAGAAGCCGGGCACGCCACGCUUGGCUCUACCAGGCUGAGGAAGAGUUUGAGAAGAGGCAGAAAGAUAAUCUCGAACUCCCGUCAGCAGAGCACCAGGCCAUCGAGAGCAGCCAGGCCAGUGUGGAGACCUGGAAGUACAAGGCCAAGAAUUCCCUCAUGUACUAUCCAGAGGGUGUCCCUGACGAGGAGCAGCUGUUUAAGAAGCCCCGGCAGGUGGUACAUAAGAACACGCGCUUCCUUAGGGACCCCUUCAGCCAAGCCCUGAGCAGGUGCCAGCUCCAGCAGGCAGCCGCCCUCAAUGCCCAGCACAAACAGGGCAAGGUGGGCCCCGAUGGCAAGGAGCUGAUCCCCCAGGAGUCCCCUCGAGUGGGUGGAUUUGGAUUUGUUGCCACUCCUUCCCCUGCCCCUGGUGUGAACGAGUCCCCGAUGAUGACCUGGGGGGAGGUUGAGAACACACCCUUGAGAGUUGAAGGGUCGGAAACGCCCUACGUGGACAGGACACCCGGCCCAGCUUUUAAGAUCCUGGAGCCAGGCCGCAGGGAGCGGCUGGGUCUGAAGAUGGCCAACGAGGCCGCUGCCAAGAACCGGGCCAAGAAGCAGGAAGCCUUGCGGAGAGUGACGGAGAAUCUGGCCAGCCUCACCCCCAAAGGCCUGAGCCCAGCCAUGUCGCCAGCCCUACAGCGCCUUGUGAGCAGGACGGCCAGCAAGUACACAGACCGGGCCCUGCGGGCCAGCUACACACCAUCCCCAGCACGCUCCACCCACCUCAAGACCCCGGCCAGUGGGCUGCAGACCCCCACAAGCACACCGGCGCCUGGCUCUGCCACACGCACCCCUCUCACACAGGACCCGGCCUCCAUCACGGACAACCUGCUGCAGCUCCCUGCCCGGCGCAAAGCUUCGGACUUCUUUUAGAGCCAGGCCUGGGCUGGGCUCAUAGACGCUUCACAGAGCCUGCAGGGCAGCUGUACACCCAGCAGAGGACUCCAGCCUUCUCGGGGCCCAGGCCUGGGCCAGAAGCUGUUGACCAUACCAGGAGUCACUGGAGAAAGGGGCUGUGCUGGGGCCAGACUGGCACAAGGCACUCGUGCCCACACCACACCCCAGGGCCUUGCCAAGCUGUUUGCUGUUUAAUUGGCCCCUUGAACUGUCAUUAAAGAACACCUAGGUACAGUCUGGGGGGUUGCCUCUCCAUCUUGCUCCCCACACGAGCCCUAGCCUUGCCCUGGGGCCUGCAUCACGUCUCAGGACUGCGGGGCUUGAAGCGAGGGGCCCCCCAGGUGAGGAAGCUGCAGGUGGGGCGGCUGUGGGAGCACCGGGUGACUGGCGUUGCUUUCUGCGGCACUCGGAACCUGUGUUCUGAGUUGAGCUCACAUCCUGCAGUGCUUUCUGCUUCUCUGGGGGGAUAUGAAGGAGAAACGGAGCCCUUGGAAGUUGUACCCUUAGGUUCCCCUGCGGUUCUGGGCCCAGGUCUGCAGCCUCCACUCUGGGCUUGCCGGCUGUGAGGUGCGCUGGUUAUAGGACUGUGUGGGGGCUGCAUAUCAGGUGAUCUCAGCUAUCACCUUCUCCCAGCACCUGGCUUCCAGCUCAUGGGGUGGGACUAUCCCACUCACCCCUCUGCUAUAGGCACUGCCCAUCUUAUGCUGCUGGCCCUGGCCUCACCUGGUCACUUCCACCAACAGGAGCUCCCAGAUAACAGUGGGUUGCUGGACAGAUCAGGCUGGGACUCUUAAGGGGUGGGGGACGUGGGGCCUUCAGUGCUUUAUCCCCUAGGAAAGGGUGCACGUUAUCCCAAGGGAGCCCCCAGGAAGUGGGGAGGGAGGGGGGAGGAGCAUGUCUAGGUGCUGACCACCUGGAGCACUUGGCCAGCAAGUGGGCCGCAUGCUUUGGGAGCAAUGGGUGACCCAGCAGGAAGCACAAAAGACCGGCCAGUGUGCCAUCAUCAAGGGCUGCUGAGCAGCUUGAAGAGCCACUGGGUGGGGAGGGCACACGGGGAGGUCUCAGCUGGGGCUGCCCCUGGAGGACAGGGCAGGGAACUUGAGGGCUGAGGACAGAAAUCUCACAUGACUCCAGGAAAUAGAGGAAGAGGAGGAUGCUGAGCGAGGGAUUGUGAGGGAGUGGGGGUAGGUCAGAGGGGGCUGAACUGCAGGAAGCCAGGGGGAGUCGUGGACCACUGGAGCUGGCCAGCCCCAGGGCAUUGGGGACAAGGCCAGGUCAGAGGGAGACAGUGUGGGCCUGGUGGGUGGACCCUGGCAGAGGCCCUCUUGUCCCCCACAAGGCCAGGCCACACUGUGAUUCUGCCUGUACCUGAGCAUCUGUCCUGUGCUCCUAGGCCGGAGACCACUGUGUGUCAGGUGGGGCGGUUGGCUGAGUCCCAGAGAAAAACACUCCUCACUGGGCACUCUUGAUGCUUGCACACACCCUGUGGUUUAUUUGGUGGUCAGUAAGGAACGUCUUUGCUGCUAAGUGGAAGAAAGCUAAUGGAACGUAAUCAAAAUAGUGGUUUAAUUGACGAAUUUUACUUGCACCUGUGCCUUCUUCAGAUCCUACCUGCCUACUUAGUUUACGUGAAGGCCGACUGCACCAUGCCCCCCAACCCCGACCCCCACCACACACAACGGGGCCAUUGUCAUGCUAGGUGCUUGCUUUCCCCACCUCAGCUCCGGAGAUGUGAUGGUCUUUGGCCCUGGAGGUCUCGGCCAGCCUGUCCUCCAUCCUGUUCUCGUUCUCGGGCACCACCAGCAGCCGGUGCUGGGUUUUGGCUCCAAGCUUGUGGUCGGGCCGGUGGUCGGGCCUCAAGCCUGUCUUGGUGUCCAGUUUGCACUCAGCGCGGUACUUGCCCUCCCCCUCCCUCUUGAAGGAGGCAGAAGACGUGGCUUUGGGCUUGGGGGGCUGCAGCCACGAGUGGCUGAGGAUCUCAUCGAUGUGGAGCCGCUGGCUGACGUCGGGCUGCAGCAUGCGGUAGAUGAGGUCCUUGCACUCGCAGGUCAGGUUCUUGGAGCGCGGGAAGUCCACACGGUGCUCCUUCUGGAUACGCAGCAUCUUCCUGAUGUCGGAGUCGUCAUAGGGCAUGGAGCCGCAGACCAUGAUGUACAGGAUCACGCCCAGGCUCCAGAUGUCAUACACCUUGGGCUGGUAGGGGAUGCUCUGCAGCACCUCGGGGGCUGCAUAUGCUGCCGACCCGCAGAAGGUCUUGCUGAGGAUGAUGCGCCCAUUGCUGUCCCGCAGGCAGCGCUUGGAGAAGCCAAAGUCAGACAGCUUGAUGUUGAAGUCCUUGUCGAGGAGAAGGUUCUCGCACUUGAGGUCCCGGUGGACGAUGUCCAGGUCGUGGCAGUACUUGACGGCGGAGGAGAGCUGUCGGAACAUCUUGCGUGCCACGUCCUCAUGCAGGGCUCCCUGGCACUUGAUGAACUCGAGGAGGUCGCCCUGGACGCCAAGCUCCAUGAUGAUGUAGAUCCGUCCGUCAGAGGUCUCAAAGAUCUCGUAAGUCUUGAUGAUGGAGCCGUGGUUGACAGUUGCCAGGAUGUCCAUCUCCCGAGGAAGGAAUCUCUCCACAAAGUCAGUAGGUGUUUUCUUGCGGUCGAUGAUCUUGACAGCCACAUUGAACUUGAGGCGCUCAGAGUAGGCAGAUUUGACUUUUGCGUAGGAACCCUUGCCAAGAUUGAUGCCUACGAUGUAACCCUUCUUCCUUAGGACUGUGGCAUCGUCCAUGGUGCCAGGAGCGACUGGCGCCGCUGCCGUCUACAUCCCCCCGUCAUGUGGGCCAGCAGGCAUUGUCCUCAUUUACACUACCGGAGGCGUCUGGCUGGGCUGCCCUGGGCUGGGCUUCGACUCAGGGGUGGAACACUCAGCAUUGUCUCCGGGUGACUUCAGCCAAUGAACUCAUAAAGCCAAGGAGUGGGGGCGGGGACUGGGCUGAGGGAGAACAGGGUCUCUGGAACCGUGGAAGCCAGGCUGGUCUGGCAGGAGCACCCACUCCCCGCCCGCUGGAAGGAAGCCUGUCCCCAGGACAGGACUCUGGUGGCCCUGCUGCUGCUGCAUUGGUUUCCCUGUCACAAGUCAAGCUGGAGGGGAGGCGGCCCACGUCCAGCCUGUUUGCAUCACCUGGCUGUGGGGACUGACCCUGCAUUGGUCUUUGUCCCACUAGGGUGGGUUUCCUGCAGCUUCUUUGGCUAUGAAGAAAAGCACCCCCAGGGCUGUGUCCUUGGUGUGGUAGGACAGUUGUCCCUGACAGUCACCCAGACAGGCCUGCAUAGCACCCCAGUUACACAGACAGAUUUCCACAGCACUGCCUUACCAUUGAGCACAUAGUUAAAUCUAGGGAAAUCAGUGCCCAGACAUCAAAGCUAGAAAUGAAACAUGGUCAGCAGGAGCCUUGCAUGGGCUUCUCUUUUGCUGGAGCAAGCCAAAAUAAUAGGAACGGUUUUACAUUCCUAGUGCCAGGACCCAUCUCGGGUCGACAAAAUCUGAAGACAAGUUAAGGGAACAGGCAGCUGUUUGAAUAGAUCAAUUGGAUAGUCUAAGGCAGCUCUCUGGACCAAGCUGUAAAGGAGAUACAAUCGAAAUAAUCACUCCGGUACCACAGUAGACAGGCCUUGAAGGCACUGGGCCCCUUUUAAUCGGACUUAGCAAGCAUUUUUUUUGCCUCUGACCUUCUCCUUGGAACAAAAUUAGUUACCAGUAGACUUAGGUGAUUGCUGUACUGCAUGUAGGCACAUAACCCCAACCUAUAUAAACAGUAAGAAAAUUGUAGCACUUUGAGUUGGUCUGCUGGAAUUAUCUCCAGCCUUCUCCCUGUAUCCAGUUACAGUGAUAAACUCCCUUCUUUCCUA